AAGGCGGGCGGCGCCGCCGACAUGACGGACAACAUCCCGCUGCAGCCGGUGCGCCAGAAGAAGCGGAUGGACAGCAGGCCCCGCGCCGGGUGCUGCGAGUGGCUGAGAUGCUGCGGUGGAGGGGAGGCCAGGCCCCGCACUGUCUGGCUGGGGCACCCCGAGAAGAGAGACCAGAGGUAUCCUCGGAAUGUCAUCAACAAUCAGAAGUACAAUUUCUUCACCUUUCUUCCUGGGGUGCUGUUCAACCAGUUCAAAUACUUUUUCAACCUCUAUUUCUUACUUCUUGCCUGCUCUCAGUUUGUUCCCGAAAUGAGACUUGGUGCACUCUAUACCUACUGGGUUCCCCUGGGCUUCGUGCUGGCCGUCACUGUCAUCCGUGAGGCGGUGGAGGAGAUCCGAUGCUACGUGCGGGACAAGGAAGUCAACUCCCAGGUCUACAGCCGGCUCACAGCACGAGGCACAGUGAAGGUGAAGAGUUCUAACAUCCAAGUUGGAGACCUUAUCAUCGUUGAAAAGAACCAGCGGGUCCCUGCCGACAUGAUCUUCCUGAGGACAUCAGAAAAAAACGGGUCAUGCUUCUUGCGGACGGAUCAGCUGGAUGGGGAGACGGACUGGAAGCUGCGGCUUCCCGUGGCCUGCACGCAGAGGCUCCCCACGGCCGCCGACCUUCUUCAGAUUCGAUCGUAUGUGUACGCAGAAGAGCCAAAUAUUGACAUUCACAACUUCGUGGGAACUUUUACCCGAGAAGACAGCGACCCCCCGAUCAGCGAGAGCCUGAGCAUAGAGAACACGCUGUGGGCUGGCACUGUGGUCGCAUCAGGUACUGUUGUGGGUGUUGUUCUUUACACUGGCAGAGAACUCCGGAGUGUCAUGAAUACCUCAAAUCCCCGAAGUAAGAUCGGCCUGUUCGACUUGGAAGUGAACUGCCUCACCAAGAUCCUCUUUGGUGCCCUGGUGGUGGUCUCGCUGGUCAUGGUUGCCCUUCAGCACUUUGCAGGCCGUUGGUACCUGCAGAUCAUCCGCUUCCUCCUCUUGUUUUCCAACAUCAUCCCCAUUAGUUUGCGUGUGAACCUGGACAUGGGCAAGAUCGUGUACAGCUGGGUGAUUCGAAGGGACUCGAAAAUCCCCGGGACCGUGGUUCGCUCCAGCACGAUUCCUGAGCAGCUGGGCAGGAUUUCGUACUUACUCACAGACAAGACAGGCACUCUUACCCAGAACGAGAUGAUUUUCAAACGGCUCCAUCUCGGAACAGUAGCCUACGGCCUCGACUCAAUGGACGAAGUACAAAGCCACAUUUUCAGCAUUUACACCCAGCAAUCCCAGGACCCACCGGCUCAGAAGGGCCCAACGCUCACCACUAAGGUCCGGCGGACCAUGAGCAGCCGCGUGCACGAAGCCGUGAAGGCCAUCGCGCUCUGCCACAACGUGACUCCCGUGUAUGAGUCCAACGGUGUGACUGAUCAGGCUGAGGCCGAGAAGCAGUACGAAGACUCCUGCCGCGUAUACCAGGCAUCCAGCCCCGAUGAGGUGGCCCUGGUACAGUGGACGGAAAGUGUGGGCUUAACCCUGGUGGGCCGAGACCAGUCUUCCAUGCAGCUGAGGACCCCUGGCGACCAGAUCCUGAACUUCACCAUCCUACAGAUCUUCCCUUUCACCUAUGAAAGCAAACGUAUGGGCAUCAUCGUGCGGGAUGAAUCAACUGGAGAAAUUACGUUUUACAUGAAGGGAGCAGAUGUGGUCAUGGCUGGCAUUGUGCAGUACAAUGACUGGUUGGAGGAAGAGUGUGGCAACAUGGCCCGAGAAGGGCUGCGGGUGCUCGUGGUGGCAAAGAAGUCUCUUGCAGAGGAGCAGUAUCAGGACUUUGAAGCCCGCUACGUCCAGGCCAAGCUGAGUGUGCACGACCGCUCCCUCAAAGUGGCCACGGUGAUCGAGAGCCUGGAGAUGGAGAUGGAACUGCUGUGCCUGACGGGCGUGGAGGACCAGCUGCAGGCAGAUGUGCGGCCCACGCUGGAGACCCUGAGGAAUGCUGGCAUCAAGGUUUGGAUGCUGACAGGGGACAAGCUGGAGACAGCUACGUGCACAGCGAAGAAUGCACAUCUGGUGACCAGAAACCAAGACAUCCACGUUUUUCGGCUGGUGACCAACCGCGGGGAGGCUCACCUCGAGCUGAACGCCUUCCGCAGGAAGCAUGAUUGUGCCCUGGUCAUCUCGGGAGACUCCCUGGAGGUUUGCCUCAAGUACUAUGAGUACGAGUUCAUGGAGCUGGCCUGCCAGUGCCCGGCCGUAGUCUGCUGCCGAUGUGCCCCCACCCAGAAGGCCCAGAUCGUGCGCCUGCUUCAGGAGCGCACGGGCAAGCUCACCUGUGCAGUAGGGGACGGAGGCAAUGACGUCAGCAUGAUUCAGGAAUCUGACUGCGGCGUGGGAGUGGAAGGAAAGGAAGGAAAACAGGCUUCGUUGGCUGCAGACUUCUCCAUCACUCAAUUUAAGCAUCUUGGCCGGUUGCUUAUGGUGCAUGGCCGGAACAGCUACAAGCGGUCAGCCGCCCUCAGCCAGUUCGUGAUUCACAGGAGCCUCUGUAUCAGCACCAUGCAGGCUGUCUUUUCCUCCGUGUUUUACUUUGCCUCCGUCCCUCUCUAUCAAGGAUUCCUCAUCAUUGGGUACUCCACAAUUUACACCAUGUUUCCUGUGUUUUCUCUGGUCCUGGACAAAGAUGUCAAAUCGGAAGUUGCCAUGCUGUAUCCUGAGCUCUACAAGGAUCUUCUCAAGGGACGGCCGUUGUCCUACAAGACAUUCUUAAUAUGGGUUUUGAUUAGCAUCUAUCAAGGGAGCACCAUCAUGUACGGGGCGCUGCUGCUGUUUGAGUCGGAGUUCGUGCACAUCGUGGCCAUCUCCUUCACCUCGCUGAUCCUCACCGAGCUGCUCAUGGUGGCGCUGACCAUCCAGACCUGGCACUGGCUCAUGACAGUGGCGGAGCUGCUCAGCCUGGCCUGCUACAUCGCCUCCCUGGUGUUCUUACACGAGUUCAUCGAUGUGUACUUCAUCGCCACCUUGUCAUUCUUGUGGAAAGUCUCCGUCAUCACUCUGGUCAGCUGCCUCCCCCUCUAUGUCCUCAAGUACCUGCGAAGACGGUUCUCUCCCCCCAGCUACUCAAAGCUCACAUCAUAGGCCGUGCGUUCGCUGGAGGGGGCCCUGGUCUUGGCGCUUCCCUGAUGGACAGAGCUCAAGUUCCAUUUAUAUUAACCGCCACCUGUGGAUUUUGCAGUAAUUGCUAACACAUGCAGUUUUAAUGGGAAGUGGCUCUGCGCCUAAACGGAGUCCUAACGCUGCAUCAACGGGAGGGAGGGUCCUGAAAGAGACCCAUCUGGGCCUGUCUGAACCCCUCGUUCUUCAUGUUUAGGUGAAUAUGAAUAUGUUAAAGCUGGUGGCUCAGCUGGGAGAUUUAUAUGGGUCACUGUGCGAGCUUCCUUAUGACUUGAAUUUUGUUGUCACAUGAUAAAAGUUUCUGUGUAGCUGAAGGUUGUAGAAGGCUUGUGUGUGUGUGUGUGUGUGUGUGUGUGUGUGUGUGUGUUUUUAAAGAGUCCUAAUGUGUAUGUACUCUUUAUGUCUUUCUUGCUCUUACAAAGAGGUGUCAGAAAAAUAGAAAGCUCUUGGUGUCGGUUUGGGAGGAAAAGACAGUGACAUUUGGUAAAAAGUUAUCCACACAAUAAUCUCCAUUCGGAAAUGCUCAGUAUCGUCUCCAGCCAGCCCUGCUUAUCCAGGUUACACUGGAUUCCUGGGAUCGUAACCAGUAAAUGAGAGGAGAGGGAGAGAGAGUGUCCUAAGUCCAAUCUGUUAUCCUUGAUCUGAUUCAGCAUCCAUAGUGUGUGAGUUAACUUCACCUGCCACCUCGUAAAAGAAUUUCAGAGGUGUGAUCCCGCUUUAUUGGGACCUGGUAACAAUCACAAAGCCAGUGGCUGUUUGAGAAGGACCUCAGACAUUUUCAGCAGAGUUGUUUUAGCAGGAAACGUGCCACUGAAUGGCCCCUAAAUGUGUCGACAGUGUGAUAAGAGACUCAACUAAUUCUUUAGGCAACAUGGCAGAUGUGACUCAGAUCCUCCAAGACCAAAGCGGAAAGGUCAGGGGGCUGGGACUCUUCUCUUCCAUAGAAGCCUGUUUCCUGUUAGGAGGCAUAAUGGAAGAUGACCCCACAAAGGCAGAGGCAUCUUUCGGAACAACACUGGUGGCAGCUUUCAGAACAAGGAACCCCUGGUGGGAGGACGCCCAAGCUACAGCGUUGGGAUCUGGGAUCUGUUCCACUGCCGGCAGAUUUCAAGGGGAACUUGCUGAAAGGCAGCCAGUGGUGAAGAUUUCUCCCCUCCCAGGAUGGACUACAUGCCGGCAUGUUUCUUAUAAAGCUGUGGCUGCUUGUUUCAGAGGAAGGGAGUUUGCAGUCGCGGGACGUGGUAGAGCAAGGCAUUCUUGGGUUUUCAAGUUGCUUCUUGCAGAAGCCACAUAUGCAUGCCAUAAGGGUUAAGUUGGUGGAUCUUUAAGAGCCAAGUGUGGUUGAGAUCUUGGAUUUGCGUUUACUUCUUGAUGAAUACAUAUCCUUCAAACCCUCUGCCUGGCGCUACUUCUGUGUGCUUCAGAGAUGUACAUCACAGCCUGGUUUCUGAUGCCUACUAACUCCUGCUCUUGGAGAGCUGGAGACACGAGGAUCAGAUAGUCCCUUGCCUUUGGAGCACUCUUGAUAAGCUUUUGUAUUUUGUGUUGUCCUUUUAAAAUGUUCUAGAAUGACUUUACGUUGCAGGUACUGGUUAAUUGGCUGUUGACACCACAUCUAUUUUGUCUUAUGAUUCUGCAGUUUUGCAGUACUUUUCUCUAUCUGAUUCAGCCAUUUCUGCCAGAGGGAAAAGGUCGGCAGAAAAGAUGUAUUGAGUGAAUAGUUAAGGAUAGGAUCUUUGUCCAAAAAUUUCAGAAAGAUUGAGCAAAUCUGACGUAUUCAUUGAGUGAGUUUCUGUGUUUUCAAAGGUGGAGGAGAAAUUUGUGCUGGAAGUUUUUAAGCCUCCGUUUUCUUGGAAAUCAGUCUGUAACACUGGCAAGUCUUAAGAUAGUCCCAUUUAGACUUUGCAGAUGCUGAACCUGGCUCUGUAACGCUGGGAAGUCUUAAGAUAGUCCUGUUUAGACUUUGCAAACCCUGUACCUGGCUUUGCUCGGAGAUUCGGGAUGCUGGCUCCUGCAGGCAGGGCGUGUGGGAGCCUCGUCAGAAAGUUUUAGAGGUUUCCAGCAGAAGCAGAAUGAAGAUGGUCUCCCUGGCCUUUUCCUUAAUUCUCAAUUUUGAUUGAGGUGCACAAGUUGACUUUUAAAGCCAACGCUUAAGAUACUGAUUGACAUCUUCAAGGGAGAAUGCUCCCAGGAGGGGCUGAAGAAGCCAUAGUUGGAAGUGGAAGGUACUCGUCAGUGUUCUCCACAAACCUUUUUACUCUGUUGUCUCAGCCGCACUGGGGCGGAGGCGGUCAAGGGUGAGAAGUACCGACACUCAAGUGCAAACUGCCACGUCGUUGGCCCAUCCCAUCAGUGGGCAGCUGGCUGACGCCAUUCACUGGACGGUCCCUGAACACCUAGGAAUGCACACACCGUGCUUCUCAGACACUGGAGACGCAAAGGCAGGAGGAUGCAGUCCGGUGAGAGGACACGAUCUUUACCUGCACAAUCAGACUGUAAGCCCAGCAGAGAACCCCAGGGGCGCCUGGGUACUUCUCGGAGGUCAUCUUAGUUGUGGUGGGGAAGACAAAGAAAUAAGCAAACAAGAAACUAGAGUUACUAUACAAGAAACUCUCCUGAGUUUGUAAACCUUAAGCAUAAGGAUUCAGUUGACCUUUUUCUUGGUUCAUCAAUCUGGAAAGAACUUACAUAAAGCGCCAUUGACACUGUCACCUGGGAGCUCCAUGGGCCGUAAGUCUUUGACAGCCAAUUUAAUUUGAGGUCAGAGGGCCUUGAGGUACACAGUCAGCACUGUUUGAACACUUUUCCUGAAAGCAAAACUCACAGCUCCCUGCGCCCUCUGACAACACUAGCUAUUUCUGCCAGAGUAAGAACUUCUAUUACUAUUUUAUUAUUGUUCAUAUGUCUUUUGAUGAUGGUUGUGUGACAGGGGGAAGCAGGAUCUAUUUGGUUUCUUCCCCUCCCCCCACCCCUUCCUUUUUGUCUCUCUUUUUUUUUCUCUAAGAAAAUCACCAGACUAGUUUUUCCAUCUUGAGUAAUUUCUUAUGUGGGACAGUUUUGAUCCUCAUUUUGAAAGCAUGCGUGUGCACAUGUGUGUUGCCUGUGGUGCCAGGUGAGACAGGUGGCACUAACUCCAGCUGCUUGGAAGGCAUCCCAAGGGCGCAUCUUAAAGUUGGAGCAGACCUCCCUUUUCCAGCCCCUGGGGCCAUUAGACCACGUGCUGGAACUAGCAUUGUAAAAUUCCCAUCCCAGUUCCACUCCCCUGAAGUGAAACCCUUUUUUUUUUGUGACAGUAAAUCUUAAAAAUCAUUGUCUCUUUAUGAACAUUUCCUCAGUUUCUUCUCUGCUGAAAAUGUAAGCCAUGCUACUUUUUAAUGUAUUUUGAAUUUUGUGCUCAUUGGAAAUUGAUAUGCUAAUGCCUCCCCCACCCCCCGCCAGACUUUUCUUUUUAUACUUUGUCUUGUUUUUACUGGGGUAGGCUGGGCAUGCGUGCGUGCCUUUAGGGCAGCAUUUUAAACCUUUGCCAAAAUUGCAAAUGGGACAUGUACAUUCUUCUGCUCCAUCCUACUUAAACACCUAUCAGCUAUUUUUAUCUUUAACCUUUUCUGUAUGUUUGAAGUGUGUGGGGGGUGUGUGUGUGUGUGAAAGAGCGAGAGAAUGAUGUCAUCUAAAGUUUUUUGAAGAAUUAUUUGGUUUUCAUUGCAUUAAAAUUCUAUCACUCCCAGCUUUGUUUUCAUUUAAAAAAAUAUACAAAGAGCUUUGUAAAUACAACACAUUUUAUUUCUCCCCCUUCUUUUAAUGUACAGCUUUUUUGCCACUUAUAUAUACUUAAAAUAUUCCCAUGAAUUAUGUCCAGUUCUUCUUGGAAAAAAAUUUGGUUUUGAAUGAACCUGCAAAGCAUCCUGCAGCGUGAGCAGCUCCUCCACCUGGAGCUCCGAAGCAUCUUCUCAGGCCAAAGCGGCAUUACCCGUGAAUCUGUCUUCUCCGCCACAGCAUGGUUUGAGGCGCAGUCUGUUAAUAUAGCUGGGCCAUGUCAGUGACUGUUGUGUUUGUGGGGUCAGGUGGGGGGCAUGGUAUUUGCAAAAAAAACAAAUUAUGGCUAAUUUAUUAUUUUGUUGCAGUGGGGUUAACUGUAAACUCAUGUAAGAGUCUGUGAUUUCCUCAUUGGUUGAUCUCUCUCUCUGUAAUCCUCAUUGCAAAUUUUCACCAGGACAGCGUUUUUUGAUUAGAGGGGAGCUCUGGCACAGUAUGCUUUAAUUUAGCAGGAACUUCCAGAUGAUUUAAAUUCUCGAUGCUGUGAUGACACACAUAUGAUCUUUCGUGUUUCUGAGCGACUCUACUUUCAUUGUUUGCCAGCGUGGCUCGUUGCUGUUGCCCAAUAAAGCUUGUGUACGUUCUGCCUUGGGGGAUUAUUUUAAUUUGUACAGAAACAUGAAUUCUGGUAUCAAAAUGAGGACUUUUUAUUAUAACGCUCCUAUUUUUUCUUUAUUUCAUGGUACAUGAAAUGUAAAGAAAACUCUUUCCAGUUCAGAAAAUUAUUUUGAUUUUGGCAAAAAAAACCCCAAAUCAAUGCAUGUUAUUUAUUAUUUUGUACUAUUGUCCAUCCCAGACGUGUCAGAAUUUCAAAAGGUGAUAGAUAUAAAUGGAAAAUAAGAUGAAAA